AGUCUGUCCUUCGGGUCCUCAGCACAGCCGUGCCGGUGAGGCGGGCGGCGGGGGAACGCGGCUGUCCCGGGUCAGGGGUCUUGCGGCGGCAGGGCGGGGGGCCGAGGGGCGGGGCCUGGGAGGAAGGCGUGGCCUUUGGGGACUGGGGCUCGGACUGGGGGCGGAGCCGGGGCUGGUUGGGGACCGGCCGGGUUCCGCUCCUGCUGGAGCCCGGUGCGUGGAAUUCCACGCGAGUGCCGGGGAGUUCCUGGGGAGCCGGGCUUCUCUUUUGGCCCCCAGCGUGUUGACCGAGCCCGCUUCGCACAGCCCUUCCUAGGGUGUGGAGAGCGGGCCCCGCCCUGAAGGGGCACCGUGGGCUGGGGGGCCUGUUUUGGAGCAGGCACCGGUGGCCGAGCUCCGUGACCAUGAAGGUCAAGGUCAUCCCCGUGCUCGAGGACAACUACAUGUACCUGGUCAUCGAGGAGCUCACGCGCGAGGCGGUGGCCGUGGACGUGGCUGUGCCCAAGAGGCUGCUGGAGAUCGUGGGCCGGGAGGGGGUGUCUCUGACCGCUGUGCUGACCACCCACCAUCACUGGGACCACGCGCGGGGAAACCCGGAGCUGGCGCGGCUUCGUCCCGGGCUGGCGGUGCUGGGCGCGGACGAGCGCAUCUUCUCGCUGACGCGCAGGCUGGCGCACGGCGAGGAGCUGCGGUUCGGGGCCAUCCACGUGCGUUGCCUCCUGACGCCCGGCCACACCGCCGGCCACAUGAGCUACUUCCUGUGGGAGGACGAUUGCCCGGACCCACCCGCCCUGUUCUCGGGCGACGCGCUGUCGGUGGCCGGCUGCGGCUCGUGCCUGGAGGGCAGCGCCCAGCAGAUGUACCAGAGCCUGGCCGAGCUGGGUACCCUGCCCCCCGAGACGGUGUUCUGCGGCCACGAGCACACGCUUAGCAACCUGGAGUUUGCCCAGAAAGUGGAGCCCUGCAACGACCACAAGAGGGAUGAGGAUGACGUGCCCACUGUGCCGUCGACUCUGGGCGAGGAGCGCCUCUACAACCCCUUCCUGCGGGUGGCGUGAGUAUGGCUGUUGUCCCGGGGCCUCCACCGUUACGUGGACCCUUAGGAAGGCAUCUGGGGACUGCGUGUUGGGCUGAGUGAGCAUCUCUGGCUUGGGGGAGGCUGCUCAUUAAGUGCCUGCCUGCCCGCCCACCCCUCGGCGCCAUGCUCCCGCGUGGGCAGCGGGCCCUGCGCCUCACUGCACCCCUCCCUGCAGAGAGGAGCCGGUGCGCAAGUUCACGGGCAAGGCGGUCCCCGCCGACGUCCUGGAGGCGCUAUGCAAGGAGCGGGCGCGCUUCGAACAGGCGGGCGAGCCGCGGCAGCCACAGGCGCGGGCCCUCCUUGCGCUGCAGUGGGGGCUCCUGAGUGCAGCCCCACACGACUGAGCCACCCAGACCCUCACAGGGCUGGGGCCUGCGUCCCUCCUCGUGACCUCGGCCAGCUGGACCCACAUGAGGGCCACCUCUGGAACCUUCUUCGAGGCCCUGGCCAGCCAUCUGCCCAGCCUCGGAGGGUGGGCAACCUGGUGCUUCCCGGGUGGACACACAGGACCACUCAGUGGGGCCUGUGUGGGCGCCGAGACCUGGGUGUCUGGGAAGUGGGGCACACGGGGCCUCCGAACUAUGAAUAAAGCUUUGAAAGGCC